GGUGCGGGCCGGCGCGGGAGGGCGCGGGAGGCGGGGAGCGGCGGCCUCUGAUUGGCCGGGGCGGGGGAGUGAGCGGAGUUUCCCACAAUGCCCCGGUGCGGUGCAGCCGCGGAUGGAUGCUGCGGGAAGGGGCUGCCAUUUGCUGCCCCUGCCAGCGGCGCGCGGACCUGCCCGCGCUCCUGCAGCCGCCGCCGCCGCCGCCGCCAGCCCGCCCGGCCCCUGCAGCGGCGCCGCCUGCGCUCCCUCCGCGGCCGCCGGAGCGGGCGCCAUGAACCCCAGCUCCUCGGCGGGAGAGGAGAAAGGGGCGACGGGCGGCAGCAGCAGCAGCGGAAGCGGCGCCGGGAGCUGCUGCCUGGGCGCCGAGGGCGGCGCGGACCCGCGGGGCGCAGGGUCAGCCGCGGCGGCGGGGGCCGCUGCCCUGGACGAGCCCGCGGCCGCCGGCCAGAAGGAGAAGGACGAAGCGCUGGAGGAGAAGCUGAGGAACUUAACUUUCCGGAAGCAGGUCUCGUACAGGAAAGCAAUCUCCCGGGCAGGCCUCCAGCAUCUGGCUCCUGCACAUCCCCUCAGCCUUCCUGUGGCAAAUGGUCCAGCCAAGGAGCCCAGAGCGACUUUGGACUGGAGUGAGAAUGCCGUGAAUGGAGAACACCUGUGGCUGGAGACCAACGUCUCGGGAGACCUCUGCUACCUUGGAGAGGAGAACUGCCAAGUCAGAUUUGCAAAAUCAGCUCUCAGGAGGAAGUGUGCAGUCUGUAAAAUCGUCGUCCACACCGCCUGCAUUGAGCAGCUAGAAAAGAUUAAUUUCAGAUGUAAACCAACAUUUCGAGAAGGAGGCUCAAGGUCACCAAGAGAAAAUUUUGUACGUCAUCACUGGGUGCACAGGCGUCGGCAGGAGGGGAAAUGUAAGCAGUGUGGUAAGGGCUUCCAGCAAAAGUUCUCCUUCCACAGUAAAGAGAUUGUGGCUAUCAGCUGUUCCUGGUGCAAGCAGGCGUUUCACAAUAAGGUGACCUGCUUCAUGCUGCAUCACAUUGAAGAACCCUGCUCCCUGGGGGCUCAUGCUGCUGUUAUUGUCCCGCCCACUUGGAUCAUUAAGGUGAAGAAACCUCAGAACUCCCUGAAGGCUUCAAAUCGGAAGAAGAAGAGAACAAGCUUUAAAAGAAAAGCCAGUAAAAGAGGGAUGGAACAGGAAAACAAAGGUCGUCCUUUUGUGAUAAAACCCAUCUCUUCUCCUCUCAUGAAACCCUUGCUUGUAUUUGUGAAUCCCAAGAGUGGAGGCAACCAGGGAACCAAAGUCCUGCAGAUGUUCAUGUGGUACCUGAAUCCACGGCAAGUCUUUGAUCUUUCUCAGGAAGGGCCAAAAGAUGCGCUUGAAUUGUAUAGGAAAGUACCAAAUCUGCGAAUUCUGGCCUGUGGUGGGGAUGGAACGGUGGGCUGGAUCCUUUCCAUCCUGGAUGAACUGCAGCUGAGCCCUCAGCCUCCUGUGGGGGUCCUUCCUCUGGGGACUGGGAAUGACCUGGCUCGAACUCUCAACUGGGGAGGGGGCUACACUGAUGAACCUGUUUCUAAGAUCCUGUGUCAAGUGGAAGAUGGGACAGUUGUACAGCUAGAUCGCUGGAACCUCCAUGUGGAAAGAAACCCCGACUUGCCUCCAGAAGAACUUGAAGAUGGCGUAUGUAAGCUCCCUCUGAAUGUUUUCAAUAACUACUUCAGCCUUGGAUUUGAUGCCCAUGUCACACUGGAGUUCCAUGAAUCCAGAGAAGCAAAUCCAGAGAAAUUCAACAGUCGUUUUCGAAAUAAAAUGUUCUAUGCAGGGGCAGCUUUUUCUGACUUCCUACAGAGAAGUUCUAGAGAUCUAUCCAAACAUGUUAAAGUUGUUUGUGAUGGAACAGAUCUCACCCCAAAGAUUCAGGAACUGAAGUUCCAGUGUAUAGUAUUUUUAAAUAUACCCAGAUAUUGUGCUGGCACAAUGCCCUGGGGAAACCCAGGUGAUCACCAUGAUUUCGAACCUCAGCGUCAUGAUGAUGGUUAUAUUGAAGUCAUUGGAUUUACCAUGGCCUCUUUGGCAGCCCUGCAAGUUGGGGGCCAUGGAGAGAGGCUACACCAGUGUCGAGAAGUCAUGCUUCUAACUUACAAAUCCAUCCCCAUGCAAGUGGAUGGGGAGCCCUGUAGGUUGGCCCCAGCUAUGAUUCGGAUCUCCCUGAGGAAUCAGGCCAACAUGGUACAGAAGAGCAAGAGGAGAACAUCCAUGCCUUUACUCAAUGAUAUUCAUCAGGUGCAAACUGCGGACCUGCGGCGAGUGUCUGCUCCCCCCGGCUCCUUCACCAUUCCCCAGUCUGUCCCAGAUCGUCUGAGGAUCCGGGUGAACAAAAUCAGUUUACAAGACUAUGAAGGAUUCCACUAUGACAAGGAGAAACUCCGAGAAGCUUCUAUUUCAGACUGGUUAAGAACCAUUGCUGGGGAACUAGUGCAGUCAUUUGGAGCGAUACCUCUGGGUAUUCUAGUUGUGCGUGGAGACUGUGAUUUGGAGACUUGCCGUAUGUACAUAGACCGCCUACAGGAGGACCUACAGUCAGUUUCUUCUGGCUCCCAGAGAGUUCAUUACCAGGACCAUGAAACCUCCUUCCCCAGGGCUCUCUCAGCACAGAGGCUCUCUCCUCGGUGGUGCUUCCUAGAUGCAACUUCUGCUGAUCGCUUUUAUCGAAUAGACAGAUCUCAGGAACAUUUGCACUUUGUGAUGGAGAUUUCCCAAGAUGAGAUUUUUAUUCUGGACCCAGAUAUGGUGGUGUCACAGCCGGCGGGGACACCUCCGGGCAUGCCUGACCUGGUGGUGGAACAAGCCUCGGGGAUCUCAGACUGGUGGAAUCCUGCCCUGCGGAAACGCAUGCUGAGUGACAGUGGGCUGGGGAUGAUAGCUCCCUAUUAUGAGGACUCAGAUCUGAAAGAUCUCAGCCACUCCCGCGUGCUACAGUCACCAGUCUCUUCAGAAGAUCAUGCAAUUUUGCAGGCAGUAAUAGCUGGUGAUCUUAUGAAGCUAAUAGAAAGCUAUAAAAAUGGAGGCAGUCUGCUAAUUCAGGGACCAGACCACUGUUCACUCCUUCACUACGCAGCUAAAACCGGCAACGGGGAGAUUGUGAAAUAUAUCCUUGACCACGGACCUUCCGAGUUAUUGGAUAUGGCAGACAGUGAAACGGGUGAGACUGCACUGCACAAGGCUGCCUGCCAGCGGAACCGGGCUGUGUGCCAGCUUCUGGUGGAUGCAGGAGCAUCUCUGAGAAAGACGGACUCCAAGGGUAAGACACCUCAAGAAAGAGCACAGCAGGCUGGGGACCCAGACUUGGCUGCUUACCUAGAAAGCCGUCAGAACUAUAAGGUCAUUGGCCAUGAGGACCUGGAAACUGCUGUUUGACCCUGGUAUUCGGGCAAAGAGGACAUGAGCAAGCGUAUCACAUCUGCCCUCCCUGCAAUUGGGCAGCUCCCCUGGAAGAAGCUGAUGGAAUUCAUAUAUCUGUCUCUCUCCUGCAAGAAUCUACCUGAGACCAUGCCACUAGCUUUUAAGGGCUACCAAGAUGUACAACAGAACAUGAUAGCCCAUUGAGAAGGAGGCAGGAUACCUGGAGAUUUGUGGAAUACAGUACGAGUUCCACAAAAUUUGAUCCUUAUUGCUUCCAGCAAGUAGCAUGAACUUCUGUGUUCACCUGUAUAAUUUAUUUUAAAGAUUCAAAGGAUGUUCGUAUAAAUGGCACUGCUCCAUCCUCCCCCUAUGCAUUGGUUUUUUUCCCUGUACCAUACAAUUCUACUGUAACUACCCAUCAACUUAAAGAAAAAUAUUAUCUCUUCUCUUUACAUUCAGUCUUGGAAGACCACAAGAUUGUCUGAAGGCCUUCUAAAACCUUCUGAAUGUCCUGCAGAAAUAUAACUGUAAAACCACUUCCAUUUCUAAGACUAAAUAUAUCAAGACUAUUUAGUGACUCUCUCUGCAUGUCCCCCUCACCCGCCAACCCUCCGUUUCAUUAUAUAGGAGCUGGGAAGUGCCACAUGGAUAAUGUCAACUUGUGUGCUAUAUCUCUGAGGAAUGGUGAGGUGGCAUGGGAGAUGUCUGUGCUUGGAGGUACCUCAGAGAGGUAACCCAGGGGUCAGCCCAGGCUGCUGGGCUGUAGCCAAUAGCCAUGCAGGACUGGUUCAGCUUGGGCUGUCUGUACAGCUCCGUACUGCCUAUGUGUAGCCAUCUUUGCCUUUUGCUGCAAUAGAAGAUGAGCAAAGGAUUAAACAGAGGCCCACAGCUAGUUUGCAGAACCACUCAAUUUUAAGUGCUGUUUAAAUUGCAGAGCAAAUAAUCCUGUGUGGGAACUGUGGUUACAGGAAAUGGAGCACUCUAACAAUGUUUACUUCUAAACUUUGUUGAAUGAUAAUAGAAAGCACCCUAAUUGACUUGGAAAAAAAAAACAGCAAAAGCAAAAGUAGCAACAUAUGUCAACAUAUGUCACUGAAAUAGGAAACAGUCAUUGGAAUGUUGCACAGAGGCUAAUAACUAUAGACUGUUGGAUACAGUGGUGAGAGGAGCCCCAUUUUAGGUCUUUCUUUUAGGUUUUUGGUUUUCAUUACUCCAAGUAAUCCUUGACCCAAGAACAAAGGCUUGUUGUAUGAGUUCCACUGCCAGAUUUAUGGGAUGCCUGGAUCAUUCAGAAGGAUGCUUCAACUAUUAUUUGUCAGGUCCAAAGGUCGUACUUAAUAACCCCAUUUUCUAUGUAUGGGGUAGUCUAAUAUAUUAUUUUAUCUACUUUAUUUUUCCCUUUUCAGAAAGUCCUUAGUGCAAACCACCAUUGGAAUCUAGCCAGAAAUGUCUGUCAGAUAGUUAGAAUUGUAACAUCUAAACCUGCCACGGAUCGAAUGGUACUUACAGGUACCUCUCUUAGGGACUCUGUGAUCCCUAAAAUAUCAGAAGAAAAUGUCUGUCUUUCUGUCCAAAUAUCUACUUGACUUGGGGGUAAGUCAAAAAUAAAAGUAGGUGUCCAAGGAUUUUACUUUUGGCGAAAUCUGACGUCUCCUGAGCUUAUUUUCAUUUUGUCCUUGGACAUAGCAUAGUGCUUCCCUAAUGUUUCUACAUAUGACCAUGAAUGAUAGUGUCUCUACAUUUAAUUUAAAAGUCUAAUGGUGACAUUUUGCUUAUCUGAGUCACAUUUCGGUAACAUAUCAUCAUUUUGAAAGUGCGGCUAUGACGUGCUAUAUUAAACAGGAACAGCCUUUCAGUGGAUGGGGAUUUUAUUACCACAGUCUUUCCAUAGUCAUUUCAAAAUCAAAUUGUUGGUGGGAGGAUGGAUUGGGUUGUGAGUAAUCUACUUCCAUAUAUCAGCCUCAGAAAUGGAACUAUCCUUUGGAUAUUACAGGAGACACUGCAGCAGAUUGUUUCCAGAAGCUGGAAAAAUAUGCUCCAGGAGAAUUUAAUCACUGGGCUUUUGCUGGGGGAUUUUUAGUUGGCGGGACUGUCAAGGAAAUGUGAUGACAGAAAUAUAAUCCUUAACACAAACUGGAAUCUGGCUUUGAAUGGCAUCUUCCAUUCCCUGGAUUGAGUCAAAUGUUUGGCCAAGCAGUCAGUUAUCUAGCUGUUACUGUUGGGAUGAAGAACUCUGUUUUCAUCAACUACCAUCUCACAUUUCUCUAAAUACUUCCAAGUAGCCCAGAGAAAAUUUAGGGUACAGGUGGCUAUGGGCCAAUUUCUAAAUAGCUCCAAUUGAAGACAUAAAUCUGUGUUAUGAAAAAUGAUGAGUUGGUACUGUAAGAUUCCUGAUGCAUUUGGAAAUUUUUUCAAACCAAAAAAAAAAAAGGCAUUAGAGUCCUGUGUUAUUCAUGGAGACCAAUAUUUGAUAUAUCGCUUUGAAAAAAGCAAGUACCACUAGGACUUGGGAUUUCCAAAAUAAAGUGAGCAGAAUAACCACAUGUUUAAUGGCUUCAACAUUAAACCACCUCCUGUAGCAUGUUUUAAAAAUUGGUCCUGGGCUUUGGAAAGAGCUAAGGCCUUAUGGUCUAGGAGUUUCCAUCUCAGCUUAAGUAUAUUGUAUCCCUACUAUUAGGACAUCAGGAAAGCAAGUGAUCUAGUCCUGGUCUGAAGUGCCAUGUAACUUUAACAGACAUAAAAAUAUGUACCUAUAGAAAUAUCAUUUCUACAAAGCCUACUGAGACAGCACUGAAGAGGCAGCUAGCUUGGCUGACUCCUCUGUGUUUGUUUCUUUGUGUCAUGGCACUGACUGCUUUGAGAUUCCAUUUUUAGAUGUGGUUGAUAGAGGAAUGGAAAAUGAAGAGUUAUUAAAAGACAACAUUCUGUAACCUGAAAGGUAGUCAUUUUUGCAAGCUUAUAUUUUAAUAUUGUGCAUUUAACAAAAUAGAACACAGUUAAACUGUGCUUUAUCGUAUUCAAGGACUUCAUAAAGAAUAAGAGAGAAGAUUAGUAAGCCAAGAAUGGAAUAAAUACCAUGACUAGGAAUUUUGCUUUCAGAGCUUAUGUUUCCUCUGUAGAUGUGAUAACCAAAAACCAGUGCAAGUUUUGAAACAUAAUUUAGCUGGCAAAUGCACAGUGAUGGAAAUUAGUAAUGACUGAUGGAGAGCCGUACAUACCUGUUGCUCCUUAUCCUUUCAGAAUGGCUGCUUUGGCAGAUCUGCCUGUGCUGGGAGCUACUCAACAUCACUUCAUUUUCAUCUGGACCUAGUGAGAGUCCCUUUGCCUAACGAAUUUCUGAAAUUUAUUUAUUUACUAGACCCCUUAUAAUAUUCAUGGCUUUAAAAAAUGACACAGCAUCUUUAUUUUAUUACAUGUCAAUUUUAUUAAUAAUAUUUAGGGGUUUUUUUAAAUUAUAAAAAUGGCACAUGCUUUUUAUAAAAUGUUUUAAUACCACAGAUGAGUAUCACAUCCACAGUCAAGGCAUCCCUUUGUUCUGGUGUUGUGUCCCACUUCCCAAAAAUAAAUACGGUUAACACUGAUGAACACUGUUGCUUGUAUGUGAUGUCAGAAAUACCCCAUCCGUUCAUGCACAAGUAUGUAUGUAUAUACGCAUAUACAUUUACACACAUAUAUAGACAUUUAUUUAUAUACACAUGCAAGUAUGUAUACUAUAUUCAUGUAUAUUGCAUAGGUUUAGAAAAGAGCAAACAUUUUAAAAGCAUGCUGAUCAUUUGUAUAUGUCUAGUGAACACCAGUAGGCAAAGACAGGUUAAACAGAGAAGUUCCAUUUAUUUUUUUGUUUCCACCAUUGCUAGGCUUAGAUCUGUUAUGGCAUUACUACAAUUGCACUUAGCAUUUUCUAUUACCUGUGUCAUAAAAUUCAUGACCAAGAGUUCCUGUAAUUGUUUAUGUUGCCUUCCAUGAAGCAUGAAACCUACCAUAGCCCCAAGACUUAUCUAUGCUAUGUUUGUAUUUCAAGUAAAGGAGAGUUCUUUCCUCUGUGAUGCUUACACCACUUUACAAGGCUGUUUGUAACACUAACACUCAGUAGGUUGCCUAGUGAUAUUUAAUUAGGGCAGGCUACUUCCGGGAAGGUGUAACUUCAGUGUAGUAUGGGGGUCUGAGCAGCUUGUCUUCCUUCCAGAAGGAGUAGCUAAUGAAAUCACUGAGAACAGCAUAUUUUAUUCAAUUAUGCUAUUUAAAAAUGGGACUUUGUUAAAAUGGCUCAUCAUAACCAUCAAAUAAAACUACUAAUUGUUCUAUUUAAAUGAAUUAUAUUCAUUUUAGGAAAAGAAGUAGAAAAACAUCUAAUAAAUUAGCUUUCUGAUUAAUCUUUAACACUUAUUUAAUAUAAAAUGGCUUCUGCCUGCAUCUUAAUUGAACCACCUUUGAAUCUCUCAACUCCUUUCACUCUGAAUCUCAUACUCAGCUGAUUAGAAGUCCUACAGGUCCUUCUCUGCCAGGUCUGUCAGAUCGACUUGGACCCUACCCUUUUCUGUGUCCCCAGUCAUCCAUUAUCUCUUGUCUCUCUAAGUUUUGGGCCAUAGCGGCAGUCCUGUCCCUGAACUUUCUGCCUACUACUGUCAAUAAUUUUGUCACGCAGUUGCAAAAAUCUUCCCCAGAUAUUAUGCUCAAAAUACAUCAAAAUGAAAUUACCCUCUGGGACAAGUAUACCUUUUACUCAAAGGACACAUGGAUGUCCACUGACCUUGAUCAUCUUAUAGAAUUAUGGCAAGCAUGAUUCUGAAAAUCUAUCAGGUUUAGCAAAUAUCUGUCUUAGUCCCAUGAGGGUACACAAUCACGGCUGCUGCUUCCUCAUUCAACAAUGUAAGCCACAUGCCUCUUUGACGGCACCUGGAGGACUAGGUUAUAGAUUUUACACUGCUGAGGGCCAUCUUUGGUUUUACACUGUCUCCUCACAGCUUAAUGAGAAACCUGAAAAUAAGAACCAAGAAAAGAGUCAUGCCCUUGGACAACCUCCUCUCCCAGGACACUGAGAUUUACUGACCAGGUCCCAGAAAGAAAGCAGAAAAAUAAUUCUUAGGCUCUUGUAGCAUGGAUUUUAAAAUAGAAACGUGAAAAUUGAAUGGUAUCUUCAUAAUGCAUAGACUCCAGAGUCUAUUUACAUAUGUAUUCAGUUAUGCAUGUAAUCAUAUGUCCAUGAAUCAAUCAUAAGUGCAUGUAUUUAAUCAUUAUUUGAAAAAUAUUUGUCACUCUGAGGCAGGCAUCAUACUAAGGAUAUAACAAUGAAUGUAAUAGACAAAACUCUUGAUUUCAUGAAGCUGGCAUCUAGAAGAAAAGACAAAUUCCAAUGUGAUAAGUGCAGUGCAGGAGAACCCCAGGGUGUCCAGCAUGGGCUGGAAAUUCAACCAAGGCUUUAUUGUACCAGCCACUCAUUAGCCAGCAAUGUUUUGGUUCAAUGAAAACAUAAGUAGGAAGAGAAUAAUAUUUUGCAUUUCCAUUUUACUGGAGUCAUAGUAGAUUUCUAAAAAUGUAUCUGAAACUAAGAUUUUAAAACAAGACUUAGAAACACUAUUAAAAUGAAAGCUAAGACUGAUUUAUUCUAGCUCUCAGGAUAGAACUAGGAAAAAUAAGCAGAGUUUUCAGUGGGUUUUGACUAAAUAUAAAGAAGAUGAAGUACAAAUAAUAUGUAAUAGUGGAGUGGAUAUCACAGUUAUAAACUUUCAGCCUCUGUUAGCAUUUAAACAGAGGAUACCUGACCACUCUGAGGGGUGUUGUGAUUAGGAAUAUGUGAUUUGAGGGGGCUAAAAUUAGAUGCUGUGAUUUUUCAAAAGAUAUUUUUUAAUGGCUUUGUUGAAUGGCAGGAUUUUAUUUUAAAAACUCAUGAAAAUCUUGAUUUUUGAUUUGUUAAACUUUGCUUUAUAACUGAGAAUUUUAAAAAUAUCUAGGGGAAUGGCCGUUAGUUAUCAUUUAAAAAAUUUUAAACUAAGCAUGAAUUUAAGAGCUAGUCAAAAGAAAACAUACUAAAAGGUGUAAUUUAAUUAAAAAUACUUCUGGAAGCUUAUAAAUUUUGAUCAGUAUUCUUAGUCAUUGUCAAGUAAAAUUCUAUUAGAAAUCUGUCUUACUGUCCAUCCAAUAUAAAAAAGUGCUGUGGUUUGAUAUUCUAAGAGUUAAGUGUAAUCUAGUAUAACCACAGAAGAAAAUUCUGCCUGUAAGGUAUUUGGGAGCCAAGUAAAUGUACAUGAAAGGCAAUCAUGGAAAACUCUUUGGCUUCUGCCACCAGCGUGGCAACCACAAGGGAGGUCCUACCCAUGGAAAUAAGAAAAUAGUGAUCCAAGUUUUCACCCAACUUUUGAAAUUUCAAUAUUUUGAGCCAAAUGCCUUCUGAAAUGGGAGGCUUUGAUAGUGGGAAAUACUGAAAUUAUCUUUUCCCUCAGACCUUUAGUGAAACACACAUAUAGUUUUCACUCUAUGACAGUAUAAACAACUCAAAUCUAUACUGUUUGUUAAGAACAGUUUCAAGAAUUAAAAAGUGCUUUAGCGUUAUGAUGUAUUGACAUGUUUGAGCUUCAGUUGGGGUUCAAAACAACCCCAACGAGGUGAAUAAUGCAUAUAAUACAUUUUAGAUGAAUGCACUGAAUCUCAGAGCAGUGAAUUCAGCCUGUGCAGAUUCAUAUAGCAAAUGAUAGUGCUGCAGCCAGAACUGGGUCUUUAGAAAUUACAUAUUAACAUGUUUUCUAAGUAAGUCAUUUUCCAUCAUUGCCUUCAAGGAUGUUUUAUAUCAAUUGUUCAGAUUUCCAUAAUAUAGAAGUUGCCUCCAUGAAAAAAAAAUGUUUACCUAAGUUUCCACGGAAAGAAUGAGUUAGAAAUAAGGGAGAAUGUGAAAUCAAAAAGUCAGAGUUUUUGCUGUCGGAGAGAGGCUUGUCAGCUUGUACAUAGUUCAAGCAAAGAAAAGUCUAAUGUUUGCAUACCAGGGUGGAUUUCAAGAGAAGAAAUUAACAGUGAGCGUUAAUGGCUUCUUUAACUUAUUUGUGAUUCUCAGCAUUUAAAAAAUGUUAGUCCUAUUUUUCUUCCUUUGAAGUCACUAUUAGGAUGAUAUAAUUUCUGAAUGCUGCAACAAAAAAUGUUAAAAAUGGCCCUGACAUCCAAGACUCUAUUGCUCUAAGUUUAUGGGUGGGUAUGCAAGCUAAGUGUUAUGAUAAUACAUAGUCAUAUACAUAGAGGUUUAAUACACCUAUGGGAAAUUCCGGCAUAUUUGAAGUAGAGAAAAACAAACAGGCUUGAAAUGUCCUUCAGUUCAGAAUCUCAUACUUUACAAGGGACAUUUAUGGGCAGAUUGGUGAAUAUGUAGAAGGAGGAUGUUUGAUCUGGAAAGAAGACAAAAUUGGAUUAGGAAUAAGAAUAUGUAGAGGAGUUAGGUUAAGUAGGACUGUUAGUUUCAAAUUCUGCAGGGAAGAUGAUUUGUAGAAUAAAAUAAGGAAAGAAAAGAGCAGUAACACAUGAAAAGGAGUUAGCUUUAUUACUUAUAAGGAUUUAUUUUUCCUAAACAUUGCAUCCAGAAAAACAGUUUGGGCUUUCUGAAAAACAGUGAAGUUGUUAUCACUGUUUCUUCUAGUAGUUAAGUGAAGAUUGAACAACUAACUCAGAGAUCAAAGGCAUAUCUUUAAUUGUGAGAGAUCUUGGACUAGAAAAACUCUGUGAGAUUUUCUUGGUUUAAAUGUCUAUAAUUUUAGACUGGAACAGAACUCAAUUUGAGCCUAUUUUUUUCCCCCAGGUUCCUGCCAACUAGAUAGCAAUGAAGGCAUUUUUUAAAAAAGCUUCCAUCAUUGCAAAUAUAUCCCAAAUCACUUAGCAGCGGGGAUUUCAUGACCCUAAAAAGUUGCCUUGCUUACACAAACACACCUAUGCUUUAGUAGAAACAUAUCUUUUUUAGGAGAUUUGGGAAUUGGCUAGCAUUUUUGCCAAUUGUUAGCCAAUUUAGGAGAUUUGGAAAUUGGCUAGCAAUUUUGCCAAUUGUUAGCCAAUUCCCAAAUCUCCUAAAAAAGAUAUGUUUCUACUAAAGCAAAAAGGUCACAGAUUCAGGAGUCAAAGUGAAAACAAAGGAUUUAGUGUUCUUUCCCCUACUUACUACCCAUUUGUUGUUUGGGAUGUAGAGUCAGGACUGGAGAAGAGGGUGGGAAAUUCUAUAUCCUCUGCCAAUACAGAGGCAUGGAGGCACUUUCUAUAACUUUGUGUCAUGAAACAAGACUUAACCCCAUAUCAGUAGACUAAUGUUUCUGUCAUAUUUCUGUCUAGGUGGAUUACAGUUUUAAUUGCCCAUCAUCCCUUAAUUCUGUAAUACAGCUUGAGUUCCUAGAUUUCAGGUUGACUGGGUGAGGGAGGAAGUCACUUGAGGUAAUUUUAAGAAAUGAAUCCAUAUCCAGAGUCUUGCAGAAAAGACCUGCUUCUACUCCACCUUCUUUCUUGUUCUACUUCUUGCCUCUGGUUUGGGGGCAUAAAAGAGGGGCAGAGUUGUGAGGAAAGGAAAAAAGAUUCUCAAAAGUAGUACAAUAAGAAGACCCUAGUAGUAACACAAAUUCUCAUGGUAAUCUCAAACAACUGAUAGUGUUAGCAGAUAUUGAAAAUCAAACUCAGGAAACAUACAGAAAGAUUAAAUUUGUUCAAAGUGGCUUCAAGGGGUAUUAGUUGUGAAAAUUUCAGUUUAUGCAGCAUAGAAGAAUUAGAUUGUGUGUGGAACUUGGGGGAAGUAGGGUCAGCUAAUAGAAGAACUUUUUAAUGGAGCUUUCCAAAGGACGAGGUGGUUUUUGGAAGGAGUUUGUCCAACCUCUUAUAAUACAUUAUGCCUGUCCACAAACUUGUUCUGGUCCCUGAUAAAGUUUGAAAAAAAUAAGGAAUAUUUAGGGUUUUUUCCCACAAAUCUCAAUAUAUUCACUUAAAAAUUCAGAGACUGUGACCUUGUUAUUUUGGGUUUAAAUAUACAUUUUCCUCUUAAAAAUGAUAGAUAUAUGUUUACAAAUUGUCUUUACUCUUCACUUAUAAAACACACACAUACAGAUAGGAUAGUCCUGUCAGUUUACCCUAUUUUUUGUUUCAAAUUUAUAGGUAAUUUCAAAUUUAUAGGUGUUGGUGAGAUUUAUCACUUUUAAGAUACCAUCUAGCCUUGAUAUUUGUUGUACCUUCUAUAUGCAACCAAAUGGCUCCUGAUCUCCUGAUCUUCUGGAGAUCAAAGAAUUUUUAUUCGCCACUCUCCCCACCCAUCAUUGGUUGGAUUGAGACUCUAAUUACAUACAAGCAUAAUUUCCAAUGCAAGUAGAACUUUGAUGCUCUCCCUGACUUACCGAUUAUAAGUUGGGAAAGUUUGGAUUCUUGCCAUCCUGGGGAAGGAGAUUUAGAACUCUCAUAGACAAAAUAUUCUAACACAACAGAAUAUUUUGCAAAACACAUCUUUGAAAAGUCAGGGGCCAAAAUAGUCUCAGCAAAGGUUAGCUUGGCUGUUUUUUAAAAUUACCAAUAGUUAAGUGGGCAACCAUGAAUCUGAAUAUUAUACAGACCACCACUGACUGAAACUGAGGAAAACCAUUCUUGUGAAAAACUAAGGAAUAGAGGACAAUCUCAGUUCUAAAAGAAUGAAUAUAUUUGAUUUAAUUUGAUUUCUGAGUGGGAAAACGUUCCCAGGCAUCCAGGGUACCCUUGGCUGUGGGUAUUCCACUCGCAAAGGCUACAUCUGUAUGAAGAGUUGCAGUCACAUUAUAAAGGGCUUUUUCAUGAUUUCUGAUUCUGCCCUAUCACAUCCCAGAGCCAUGCUUUUGCAAAGCUGCCAGCUGGCAGGUGGAAUCCAUAAACAAGUAGCAGCUGUGGCAGUAGAAAGAUUAAAGUUUUAUUUCCAGGUAAAGGAGGAUUCAGAUAAUACGAAGUGGAGGGAGGGUGGGUGGGGGGGGGGGGGUGGGAUGGGAAAGGGAAGAAUGAAGUUUUUUGUAACAAAGUCAUAAAGUAUUUUUCCCUAAUUUUCUUGCAUUUCCUAUUUAUAUAAAGUAUCUUGAUCACUGUGUUGCACUACAGAGAUUUUCAAUGGAGUUAAUUUGGGAGACUGAACUAAUCUCUGAAAAAGAAAUUGACUAGUUACAGUUACUUUUUGGACACUUUUUCUGUAUUGUGAAUUGUGUGGAAAUGUACAGAAUAAAAAUGAAGAAAUGUA